GCGAGACUUUCAGGGGUCGGAGCGCGGGGGCCGGCCGAGAGGAAAGCUGGAGGCGCGGGUGGGGAACAUGUCUGAGUCGGAGCUCGGCAGGAAGUGGGACCGGUGUCUGGCGGAUGCGGUCGUGAAGAUAGGUACUGGUUUUGGAUUAGGAAUUGUUUUCUCACUUACCUUCUUUAAAAGAAGAAUGUGGCCAUUAGCCUUCGGUUCUGGCAUGGGAUUAGGAAUGGCUUAUUCCAACUGUCAGCAUGAUUUCCAGGCUCCAUAUCUUCUACAUGGAAAAUAUGUCAAAAACCUGCUGAAACCGUCAGCUGCCUGCAGCCAGCCCAUGUCUGCUGGAGAGAUGGGAGUAGGGGAGCCAUCUCUGCACCAAAGCAAGAGUGAGGUCAUCACAGGGACCAUGCAAGAAGAGGCGCAGCUGUGUGGCACUGAAGCCGGCAGCCGGCCUUUUCCACCACUCCCUGGCUCCUCGCUUUCCUGGCAUCAGAGCUGAUUGUGGGGAGAACCGAAAGGAGCAGACAGAGAAGCUUCAGGAGCAGGAGCAGUGACUUCACCUGAGAACAUCCCAGCGGGAGGACAAGAGAAAUCAUGUUUAUUCCUCAGGAAUACUGAAGUGCCCUGGAGUAAGCUGCCAUUCUUCUGUAACAAUGUUAUCAGUAAUGCUUUAAACUCCAGCACCUGGUUAUGCAUUUGAAACCAAGUCUGUUUCUUGUUUUGUAUUUUCUCUCUGGAAGUUGUAAGGAGGUGGUCUUAAAUAAAUUAAACAAAAAGAGGAAGUCCAUUGCAUGGCCUUUGUUUCUUCACCUUUGGUCUCUGAGCAUGAGGAGGACUGUGUGUGAACUGCCAGCAGCUGUAGCCACCUGCUCACAGCCUCUCUGAGAACCCCCUGAAACCAGUUGUUGGGUAUCCUUCCCAUUUGCCCCCUCAGGCGUAGUUUUCAGAACUGCUUCCACCUCGUAAUCAGAAGUUGAAGAUUGCUGCUGCGUGGCCUGAUGGAGAUGACUGAUGUCUUAAGGCGCCUUUCCUUCUGUGGCACCUCUUCGUGUGUUCUCACCUGGGGACCUGGCAGGGCACAUCUCCGCUGUGCCUACUGCAAGGCGGUCCCACUGCUGCUGUAUUAGCAGGGGAAGAAUCCUGGCUGUGUGGAUGGCCCACUCCAUUGAAGUCAAGUCCUGCAGCUUCAUAGAGCUUGAGACAGUCCAAGCUUCAGCUCUGGAGGGCGGAGGAAAGCUCAUGGCAUACCCACCUGGCCGGAGGAGCCCGAUUGGGGUUAAUUUUAUCUUCACGUAGCAGCUGAAGUUUGAGGACAAAAGGGCCACUUCUGAUGCCCCUCUGAGUUUGUUCCUGUGGUUUCACUUGAACCAGGGAUGCUAGAUGCAAAAGUCAUAUUUUAGCAAUUUCUUCAGACGAUAUACAGAACCCCAGCGCUCAGCCGUUCUUAUUUCUUUUUCCUUAUCGUAGAAUUAAGAUAGGGAGAGCCCGAUCCCACUUGCCCCUGUAUCCUGUAAAUGUUGAUUUAUCAUCUACUGUAAGCGAGGCACUGUUGUAAGCAGCAGAGAUAAAUGGAUAAAUAGACACAGGCUUCUGCCUUCAAGGAGCUUAGAGUCUGAUGGAAAGACAGACGUGCAAACACAACUCUGAAAGAAGUGUUUUAAUGGAGAAGAGAGGUGUAGGCAAAGUACACUGAGAACAAAGGAGAAGGAGCAACUAUGUCUCCCUAGGAUGGCCCCACAGGCGACGGAAUGCCUGCGCUGGGACCCGAAGUUGACUGGGAAUCCCAGACAGAAGGAGGGUAGCCUCUGUGUUUGCUCAGGAUCAUGUAAUGCAUAUUAUAGCUGGGAAAUCGCAAGUAGUUCAGCAUAGCCAGGGUGUGUAGGGGCAGGGGAAAGGCAUGGAGGGGGAGGCUGGGCAAUAGGGUACAACUCAUGUCUGACUCCAGUUCUGGAACAUUGAUUAGACCUUAGUUCUUGCAAGUGCUAUAGUGAGUACAUUCAGGGUAGCAAAUACCCUCCCUCAGCCUCCCCACUCCCUUUUCCAGAAAGGUCUGCUAGGCUCUGCCCUGCAAACUGUCCAGGCUCCUCUGCCCUCUGGGCUUGUUUUCCUCUUUAUUGCUACUUGGCUGUUUUUCACUUGGUCCUCUUCAUUCUAUGAUUAAGGCAACCCAUAUAAUUGAAAGAAAAAUAAUGUGCAGCCUGUUUCAUCCCUUCCACUUGUUUUCUUACUAUUUAUUUAUUUAUUUCUGAGAUGGAAUUUUGCUCUUGUUGCCCAGGCUGGAGUGCAAUGGUGGCGAUCUCGGCCUGCUGCAACCUCCGCUUCCUGGGUUCAAGCGCUUCUCCUGCCUCAGCCUCCCGAGUAGCUGGGAUUACAGGCAUGCGCCAUCACACCUGGCUAAUUUUGUAUUUUUAGUAGAGACGGUGUUUCUCCUUGGUCAUGCUGGUCUCCAACUCCCGACCUCAGGUGAUCCUCCCGCCUCGGCCUCCCAAAGUGCUGGGAUUACAGGCGUGAGCCACCGCACCCAGCCUCCUAUUUGCUUUAAAAGUAAUUUCCUGGCCGGAUGCGGUGGCUCACACCUGUAAUCCCAGCACUUUGGGAGGCCAAGGCAGGUGGAUCAUGAGGUCAAGAGAUCAAGACCAUCCUGGCCAACAUUGUAAAACCCUGUCUCUACUAAAAAUAUAAAAAUCAGCUGGGCAUGGUGGCGCACACCUGUAGUCCCAGCUACUCAGGAGGUUGAGGCAGGAGAAUCAUUUGAACCCGGGAGGCAGAGGUUGCGGUGAGCUGAGAUCGCGCCACUGCACUCCAGCCCGGCGACAGAGCGAGAAUCUGUCUCAAAAAAAAAAAAAAAAAAAAAGCAUUUUCCUUCCCCAAUUUUUCUGUCAUUUUCCCAUCCUCAUUCAGGCAGAGAGAAGAAUAACAUGCCCCCUUCCAAAAAAGACAAAACACAAGGUAGCCACAAAUUCCCUAGACACAUUAGAAAAAUAGGGAGUGGAGAGGGGCAUUGGAAUGAAAGUUCUCUAUCUCAUUAGCUGUUAGGCUUUAGGCAUUUAUUUGGAUGGAUCCCUUUGGCACCUUGGAAGCACCACUGAAGUGCUCUGAGAAAGGGGUCAGCUGUCUGAGGGAAUAGUUCUGGAUAGAGGCCACAGGAAGCACUGGCCAGUUGCUUUAGUUCUAGAUAGCUUUGUAUUCCCGCCUUGUUGCCCUUAGCGGAGGCUGGCCCAAAGCACACUUGAUCUUGUCCCCACUCCCUGCCCCCAUCUCAGAUCAACCUUCAGAAAGUCCCGGCUUGUUGGCAAAGGCACACAUUCUGUGUUACUCUUAAGUUUCAUUAGAAAUUCAAGUCCUCUGGGGCCCUGUUCCCUUGUGGGCUUGUGCAACUGACUUUGUUUCUUGUCUGCCUUUCUGGAACCAAAUCCAAGGAAAUUCAUGGGUUUGGGGAGACAGCGAUGGGAACCCAGCAGGGCACAGGAUGCUAGGAUAAAGCUGUGGCGCCCCAAAAGUGGCCUGCUCUGCCAACAUACAUAAAUACAUACAGUCUGAGCUUGACACUGUAUAAUUUGGCCCAGAACAAUAUGUAUUUUGAGCUCAUUUAGGUGAAUGACUUUGGCAUUCCAUGUACCCACUAGGGGAAGCUUUAUCAGGCUGCAUUUGCCUUAUGCAGAAGUAUGCCUUUGUUCUGAGAAAUGGCCUCAGAACACACUGUUGAGCUGUCUCCUUUAGUGAGUGUCAUCCUCUCAUCCAUUUCAAAAGAUUGCAGAUGCCGUCUUGAAGUCCUGCUUGUAAGAAAUGCAGGGGUUGGGAAUGGAGGAGAUGACGAUGUAGUUUUGCUUUUAGUUUUCCCAAACCUGUUUACAUUUUUUAAAAAUGUAACCAACCCAUAAUUGCAUUUUACUUGUCGUGGUUCGAUCUGAUUGUAUUGUCGAAGGACUAUUUUUGAACCUGUCCAAAUAAACUCUGCAAAGUAUUUCCACAA